GCCUGUCAGGUCCAUCCGGCGAUGCUGGGUCUGGACGAGCUCGGGAGGAGUGGUUGUGGCCAUUGCACACAGGCGGAUCUGAGGUUCGGCGACGCCGCUGGUCGCGACCCGGGACAGGACAACGACAGGAACACCGCCGAGCCCGCGUUCCCCCCCCGCCCAGAGUCAUGGCGGCAGCAGCCGCUCUGAGGGCGCCUGCUCAGACUACUGUGGAUGAUGUCAGCCACAUUAUGGUGUAAGCCCUAAAGUUAAGAGCAGUGUGACCUUUGAAGAUGUGGCUGUAAACUUUUCCCUGGAGGAAUGGAGUCUUCUUAAUGAGGCUCAGAGAUGCCUGUACCGUGACGUGAUGCUGGAGACCUUGACACUUAUAUCCUCCCUGGGUUGUUGGCAUGGAGGGGAAGAUGAGGCAGCACCUUCUAAGCAGAGCACGUGUAUACAUAUAUACAAAGACCAGGGAGGUCAUAGUGGAGAAAGGCCUUAUGAGUGUGGGGAAUAUAGGAAAUUAUUUAAGAACAAGUCCUGCCUCACUGAACCCAGAAGAGAUCACAAACACAGGAAUGUUCGCACUGGAGAAAGGCCUUAUGAGUGCAGCAAAUAUGGGAAAUUAUUUCACCAAAAGCCUACACUCCAUAUUCAUGAGAGAUUUCAUACUGGGCAAAAGACCUAUGAGUGCAGUGAGUGUGGAAAAUCAUUUCACCAAAGCUCUUCACUCUUGCAGCGUCAGACACUUCACACUAGAGAAAGGCCUUAUGAGUGUAUUGAAUGUGGGAAAGCCUUUGCUGAAAAGUCCAGUCUCAUUAACCACAGGAAAGUUCACUCUGGAGCAAAGCGUUAUGAAUGCAAUGAAUGUGGGAAGUCCUUUGCUUAUACAUCUAGUCUCAUUAAACACAGGAGGAUUCACACUGGAGAGAGGCCUUAUGAGUGCAGUGAAUGUGGGAGAUCCUUUGCUGAAAACUCCAGUCUUAUUAAACACUUGAGAGUUCACACAGGAGAAAGGCCUUAUGAAUGCGUUGAGUGUGGAAAAUCAUUUCGCCGAAGCUCUUCACUCUUGCAGCAUCAGAGAGUUCACACUAGAGAAAGGCCUUAUGAAUGUAGUGAAUGUGGGAAAUCCUUUAGCUUAAGGUCCAACCUCAUUCACCAUCAGCGAGUUCAUACUGGAGAAAGGCAUGAGUGCGGGCAGUGUGGGAAAUCCUUUAGCCGAAAAUCUAGCCUUAUUAUACAUCUGAGAGUUCACACUGGAGAAAGGCCUUAUGAGUGCAGUGACUGUGGGAAAUCCUUUGCUGAAAACUCCAGCCUUAUUAAACACUUGAGAGUUCACACUGGAGAAAGGCCAUAUGAAUGCAUUGAUUGUGGAAAAUCAUUUCGCCACAGUUCUUCGUUCCGUCGCCAUCAGAGAGUUCAUACUGGAAUGAGGCCUUAUAAGUGAAGCAAAUUUUGGAAAUUCUCUUGCCCAGGCUUUUUGCUCCUUCAAGGCCAGAGAGUUCACACCAGAUCAAGGUGUUAUGAGUGUGACAAAUGGGGAAUAUUCUUUAGCUAGAAUGCUAGCUUCUUUACAUAAAAGAGUGCUCCCACUGAAGAAGUGCCUUUUGAGUGCAAUGAAUGUGAGAAAGCCUUCAGCCCUCUCUCAUUGGUUACCACAAUAUUUACAUGAGGAAAAUACCACAGAUGUGGAGGUAAUAUUAUUUUUUCUUCAAUAUAACACUGGAGGAAACCCCUUAUGAGGAUGCCAUCUGCCUAAAUUGAAUGUCAUACAUCAAAUAGCUGCAUACAUUCCAGGUAUGUGGGAACUGCAUAGUAUUUUUCGACCUGCCCAGGUCUCUUGCUAGACUUCUGUGACUUACAGUUCUCUUCUAAAAAGCAUUUCACCUUUACCACUUGGCAGGUGCCCACAGUACAUCAUUCGCCUAACUCAUCAUGAUCCAGAAGUAACUUUGAUUUUGUUUCAUUCAACAGAGGGAUUUUUUAGUAUCCUCAGCACUCAUUCUAUUCUCAUUUCUUUCUCUCCAAUGAGUUAGGCCAUGAACCUGACUCAUUUUUGGCACAGAGGACUCUUCUGAUAACUUGAAAAAAUGGACUACCUUUUUCAGGGAUCUUUUGGAUCUCACAGAGUUCUUAAGAUGGAAUUUUCCAGCCUGCCAGUCAUGAAUCUCAGACAGCCUGCCACCUAUUGCCCUGAUUUGUGUUAUAAUAAAGGCCUUGUUGCUUAAGACACCUUCAGUCUUUGCAGGAGGGCAUGGAAGCUCCAA